AGUCUCUUCCUGGCCUCCCCACAGUGCUGGCCUCUGCCUCCAUCUCAGUCACACAUGUCUAGCCUCCAGGCGCUGUGCUCUGGCCUGCCCCUGCGGCCCCUCCCAGAGAACCGGGGACGCCAGGCUGGGGUGCCCCAUGCCCCUGUCAGGACCCCCAGCCUCAGCCCUGUGGAGAAACAGCUGGCGCUGAGGAACGCCCUGCGCUACUUCCCCCCGGAUGUCCAGGAGCUGCUGGCCCCAGAGUUUGCCCAGGAGCUGCAACUGUACGGACACAUCUACAUGUACCGGUUUUGCCCCGACAUUGAAAUGAGGGCCUACCCGAUUGAGCAGUACCCCUGCCAGACGAAAGUGGCUGCCGCCAUCAUGCACAUGAUUAUGAACAACCUGGAUCCUGCCGUGGCCCAGUUUCCCCAGGAGCUGGUGACCUAUGGAGGAAAUGGGCAGGUGUUCAGCAACUGGGCUCAGUUCUGGCUGACCAUGUUCUACUUGUCGAAGAUGACAGAGGAGCAGACUUUGGUCAUGUACAGUGGGCACCCACUUGGCCUCUUUCCCAGCAGCCGCAGUGCCCCACGGCUCGUCAUCACCAAUGGGAUGGUCAUUCCCAACUACUCCUCCCGGACGGAGUAUGAGAAGCUCUUUGCCUUGGGGGUUACAAUGUACGGCCAGAUGACAGCAGGUAGCUACUGCUACAUCGGUCCCCAGGGAAUCGUUCAUGGCACUGUGCUCACCGUGUUGAAUGCUGCACGUCGGUACCUGGGCAUCGAGGACUUGGCUGGGAAGGUCUUUGUCACCUCUGGGCUCGGCGGAAUGAGUGGGGCUCAGGCCAAGGCCGCAGUCAUCGUGGGGUGCAUCGGUGUGAUAGCAGAGGUGGAUAAAGCAGCCCUUGAGAAACGCCACAGGCAGGGCUGGCUGAUGGAAGUGACUGACAGCUUGGACCGCUGCAUCCAGAGGCUCAGGGUCCUUCAGCUGGGAUUGCAACAAGCCCUGGGCUGGGCCGGCCUCCCUGCUGCCCUGGGACUGUGUGUCCUUUCCUGCUUUGUCAACCUUGCACCCCUGGGGGAGGGGAGGUGCCUGGCUCCCUCGGGCUUCUCCAGGCCACUCCUGGGGGCACCUGUUCUGCUUUUGUGUCCUUCCAGGGAAGCAAGGAAAAAAAAGGAGGUGCUCAGCCUUGGUUACCAUGGCAACGUGGUGGCUCUUUGGGAGCGCCUGGUCCACGAAUUGGACACGACGGGGGAGUGCUUGGUGGACCUGGGGUCAGAUCAGACAUCCUGCCACAACCCGUUCAAUGGCGGCUACUACCCUGUGCAGCUCAGCUUCACGGAGGCCCAGAGCCUCAUGGCCUCCAACCCUGCUGUGUUCAAGGACCUGGUCCAGGAAAGCCUGAGGAGGCAAGUCUCAGCCAUCAACAGGUUGGCCGAGGAGAAGUUCUUCUUCUGGGACUACGGCAAUGCCUUCCUCUUGGAGGCCCAGAGAGCAGGAGCGGAUGUGGAGAAGAAAGGUGCUGGCAGGACAGAGUUCCGCUACCCUUCCUAUGUGCAGCACAUCAUGGGGGACAUAUUCUCCCAGGGAUUUGGGCCUUUCCGCUGGGUGUGCACAUCGGGGGACCCCCAGGACCUGGCGGUCACAGACGAACUGGCCACAUCUGUGCUGGAGGAAGCCAUUGCUGAUGGAGUGAAGGUGUCUGUGAAGCUGCAGUACAUGGACAACAUCCGCUGGAUCCGGGAGGCCGCCAGGCACCGGCUGGUGGUGGGCUCCCAGGCAAGGAUCCUGUACUCAGACCAGAAGGGCCGCGUGGCCAUCGCUGUGGCCAUUAACCAGGCCAUCGCCUGCAGGAGGAUCAAGGCGCCGGUGGUCCUGAGCCGAGAUCACCAUGACGUGAGCGGCACCGACAGCCCCUUUAGGGAGACCUCCAACAUUUACGACGGCUCUGCCUUCUGUGCAGACAUGGCUGUGCAGAACUUCGUGGGAGAUGCCUGUCGCGGAGCCACCUGGGUCGCCCUUCACAACGGAGGGGGCGUGGGCUGGGGUGAGGUGAUCAACGGGGGAUUCGGCCUCGUGCUGGACGGUACCCCGGAGGCCGAGGGGAGAGCCAGGCUGAUGCUCAGCUGGGAUGUCUCCAAUGGUGUGGCCCGGCGCUGCUGGUCAGGGAACCAGAAGGCCUAUGAGAUCAUCUGCCAGACCAUGCAGGAGAACAGCACCUUGGUGGUGACACUGCCUCACAAGGUGGAGGACGAGCGGGUGCUCCAGCAGGCCCUGCAGCUCUGAGGGAGCCAGGAGUCGCGGCCCCUGCCUCCCUUCCUCCCUGGCGAUCCUCACCUGCCCAGCCAUGGCACACACCCUUCCUGCACACCCGCACUACCUGCACUUCUCGCACAUCCUCACGUGGCCCUUAUGGUGCCCUGUGCAGGGUGCCACCACAGCCUCAUUUUACAGACAGCCCCCUGAGGCCCAGAGACAUGCAGCUCUCUGUCCACAACCAUGCCACUUGCAUGGGAGCCCUGAAGGCUGUCAAAGUCCAUUUAGGGCCAAGUCCCAAGCCUGCCCGGGGGCCCUGCGGUGAACACUGGUCAAGCUCUCUCCGGCUGGGAUGAUCACACCCUCUGCUUCCUGGCCACCUGCCAGCCUCCAUGCAACUCUGUCUGUCUGCUGCCCAUCUGCUGUCUGUGCAAGCAACUUCUGGACCCUGGCACCCUGGGCUGCUGGCCUGGAGGAGUUCGGGAAGGAGGAUAGACCAGGAAAUAAAGGGUCAACAGAGCUGUGUGCUGCACUGUGGGCUGGUGGGACGGGCAGGCCGGGUCUGCCCUAAGGAUAAAUGAUCACUUACUGGGGAAGAAAUGAGAGAGCAGGGGCACCCCCCUAGGCCAGCACAGCCUGAGGGGUACAGCAAAGGGGACCCUUUGCUGGCCCCUGAGGCUGGAGUCUGGCACCCCUUCCCCAAUCCCAUAGCCCGGUAAUGACUGGGUCCAGAGCCUCGUGAGAGGUCACCGGGAUGGGGGAAGUGGCCUCUGUCAGGGCCAGGGCUCAUGAAUCUCAUUCUCUUAGCUGGGCGUGCAACAGACCAACAGAUAACUCAUCCUAAACAGAGAAAUGAGAAAGAGUCUGUGGGUGGGCCUCUGAGGGCCACAGAAAACCAGACACCCCACAUGUCGGUGGAUUGGAGAGGGGCAGGCCACUGCCCUCUCCAGGACCAAGCCGGGUUCUUGGUCCCCACCCUCCCUGCACUCCGCAUCUCCUCCCCAGCAGCCAUUCUCCCCUUUCCCUUGUGAACAAAAGCCUAGUUUUGUGUGGGCAGCAAUAUAGGGUAAAUAAAACCACCUGAUUCUCCAGCCUUCCUUGCUGUUAGGAGGGACUGUUGGCCUAGUCCUGGCCCACGAGAUGAGGGUGGGGUCUGUGGGGCAGGGCUUCUUGAGAGCCGUCGUUUUUCUAAUAAAAUGGACAGAUCCA